ACUUCCGGUCGCUUUCGGUCUCUCAGCGGCCGGUUUCUGCGUCCGCUGCCGCAGGUUCCACCGCGCUCCAGGUAUUUUUUUUUCUGAAGGAAAGCUGCUUCCUCAUAUGUUUCAAGAAUGGCUCUCCCUAUCAUUGUAAAAUGGGGUGGACAGGAGUAUUCAGUGACCACACUUUCAGAAGAUGAUACUGUGCUCGAUCUCAAACAGUUUCUCAAGACCCUUACAGGAGUUCUUCCAGAACGCCAAAAGUUACUUGGACUCAAAGUUAAAGGCAAACCUGCAGAAAAUGAUGUUAAGCUUGGAGCUCUCAAACUGAAACCAAAUACUAAAAUCAUGAUGAUGGGAACUCGUGAGGAGAGCUUGGAAGAUGUCUUAGGUCCACCCCCUGACAAUGAUGAUGUUGUUAAUGACUUUGAUAUUGAAGAUGAAGUAGUUGAAGUAGAAAAUAGGGAAGAAAACCUACUGAAAAUUUCUCGCAGAGUGAAAGAGUACAAAGUGGAAAUUUUGAAUCCUCCCAGGGAAGGGAAAAAGCUUUUGGUGCUAGAUGUUGAUUAUACAUUAUUUGACCACAGGUCUUGUGCAGAGACUGGGGUAGAAUUAAUGCGGCCAUAUCUUCAUGAAUUUCUAACAUCUGCCUAUGAAGAUUAUGACAUUGUUAUUUGGUCUGCAACAAAUAUGAAGUGGAUUGAAGCUAAAAUGAAAGAGCUGGGAGUGAGCACAAAUGCAAAUUAUAAGAUUACUUUCAUGUUGGAUAGUGCUGCUAUGAUAACAGUACAUACUCCAAGGAGAGGAUUAAUAGACGUAAAGCCUCUUGGUGUUAUAUGGGGAAAGUUUUCGGAGUUUUACAGCAAGAAAAACACCAUUAUGUUUGAUGACAUAGGGAGAAAUUUUCUAAUGAACCCACAGAAUGGACUAAAGAUAAGGCCUUUUAUGAAAGCGCACCUAAAUCGUGAUAAAGACAAAGAACUUUUAAAAUUAACUCAGUACCUCAAGGAGAUAGCAAAAUUAGAUGACUUUUUGGAUCUAAAUCACAAAUAUUGGGAAAGAUAUCUCUCAAAGAAGCAAGGACAGUAGUUACAAGUUAUACUGGCAGUUAUUGAAGAUACUUAAGAUCCAAGAACUUCUUGCUUUUAUGCUAGAAAUCAUUAUGAUAGUGCUGGACACUGAAGCAAAUACCAUACUGCUUAUACUUGGUCUUCCAGUUUUUUGUAAAUUUAAUUUUAUAUUUUUUGAAGAUGAUAGCAAUAUGCUAAAAAAUGCUUGUCCCCUAUAUGAAUAUUCUGUUACGCUUGAAAAAUAUUUUCUCCAGCGUUGGUUACUGACCACCCCACCCUCCCACCACACACACACACACACACACACACACACACACACACACACACACACAAAGUGGAGAAAAAUGUAUACUCAACAAUGUCAUUUUGUGACUUUGGAAACAAGUUAUGUUUUGUGUUUUUGUCUCAUUGUGUUAUUGUCUGACUAAAUCUAAAACCAAACCCAUGUUGAAACUAGUACUUUUCCCUUUAAAAACAAACCAAAAAAAAAAACAAAAAAAAACUUUUUAAUUAAAGAACCUAGUUUGCUAUGCUUAAAAUUACCAAGAAUUUUUUAUUUCUUUGUCAUAGACACAAUUUCUCUUCUGUAUGCCACUAGUUACAUUUCUAAAUUCUGAGCGGUCUCAGUUAGGCCUGUAUGUGUGUACAUGUCCAAGUAAAGCUGGAAAAUGUCAGUCUUGACACAGCUGUGUCUUAGUAUGAGAAACAGAAGACUGAAGAAUAAAAACUAAGGAACAAGAAUGAGUCUCUUUUUGGUGGCUAAGUAGAAUCUUCCUAAAACCAUUGUCAUAAAAGCAGUUAAAGGCAAUAAAUUUUUAAAAGGGACAUAUCACUGAUUCAUUCCUAAAAAGCAUGAACAAAAAGUUUUUGUUCUGUUCCAGCUAUAUCUUGUCUAAGUGCUAACACUGUUUCAGUGAAAAUAUCUAGCCAUAAGAUUAAAAAAAUAUAUUAUUUGCAAUGCUUAAGCCUGCAGAUACGUAAUGUGACCACUGUUUUGUGUUGACAAUAUUGCUUUAUACAGUUCUUGUAUUUGAAAGGAAUUGAUCCUUUUAAAGAAACAUGGUGUAUAUUGUUCUUACAGGACUAAUUUCAGUGGUGUAAAUAAUAAAUAUCUUUUCUUAAAA